AGACAGCCACAGAGCUCCUGGCGUGGGCAAGGCUGGCCAAGGAUGGCGACGCCCAGGGGCCUGGGGGCCCUGCUCCUGCUCCUCCUGCUCCCGACCUCAGGUCAGGAAAAGCCCACCGAAGGGCCAAGAAACACCUGCCUGGGGAGCAACAACAUGUACGACAUCUUCAACUUGAAUGACAAGGCUUUGUGCUUCACCAAGUGCAGGCAGUCGGGCAGCGACUCCUGCAAUGUGGAAAACUUGCAGAGAUACUGGCUAAACUACGAGGCCCAUCUGAUGAAGGAAGGUUUGACGCAGAAGGUGAACACGCCUUUCCUGAAGGCUUUGGUCCAGAACCUCAGCACCAACACUGCAGAAGACUUCUAUUUCUCUCUGGAGCCCUCUCAGGUUCCGAGGCAGGUGAUGAAGGACGAGGACAAGCCCCCUGACAGAGUGCGACUUCCCAAGAGCCUUUUUCGAUCCCUGCCAGGCAACAGGUCUGUGGUCCGCUUGGCCGUCACCAUUCUGGACAUUGGUCCAGGGACUCUCUUCAAGGGCCCCCGGCUCGGCCUGGGAGAUGGCAGCGGCGUGUUGAACAAUCGCCUGGUGGGUUUGAGUGUGGGACAAAUGCAUGUCACCAAGCUGGCUGAGCCUCUGGAGAUCGUCUUCUCUCACCAGCGACCGCCCCCUAACAUGACCCUCACCUGUGUAUUCUGGGAUGUGACUAAAGGGACCACUGGAGACUGGUCUUCUGAGGGCUGCUCCACGGAGGUCAGACCUGAGGGGACCGUGUGCUGCUGUGACCACCUGACCUUUUUCGCCCUGCUCCUGAGACCCACCUUGGACCAGUCCACGGUGCAUAUCCUCACACGCAUCUCCCAGGCGGGCUGUGGGGUCUCCAUGAUCUUCCUGGCCUUCACCAUUAUUCUUUAUGCCUUUCUGAGCCCUGGCCUAGGACAUGGUCCCCAUCCCCAACAAGCCGAGUGUGACUUGCCAGCUGGCCGCAUUGCUGGACCCUGUGAGCGGGGCUUGGAGCGCCAGGAGAAAUUACCACCAGCUCCCCAGGGUGGGGCCUGGCAUCUCAGGCUUUCCCGGGAGAGGUUCAAGUCAGAAGAUGCCCCAAAGAUCCACGUGGCCCUGGGUGGCAGCCUGUUCCUCCUGAAUCUGGCCUUCUUGGUCAAUGUGGGGAGUGGCUCAAAGGGGUCUGAUGCUGCCUGCUGGGCCCGGGGGGCUGUCUUCCACUACUUCCUGCUCUGUGCCUUCACCUGGAUGGGCCUUGAAGCCUUCCACCUCUACCUGCUCGCUGUCAGGGUCUUCAACACCUACUUCGGGCACUACUUCCUGAAGCUGAGCCUGGUGGGCUGGGGCCUGCCCGCCCUGAUGGUCAUCGGCACUGGGAGUGCCAACAGCUACGGCCUCUACACCAUCCGUGAUAGGGAGAACCGCACCUCUCUGGAGCUAUGCUGGUUCCGUGAAGGGACAACCAUGUACGCCCUCUAUAUCACCGUCCACGGCUACUUCCUCAUCACCUUCCUCUUUGGCAUGGUGGUCCUGGCCCUGGUGGUCUGGAAGAUCUUCACCCUGUCCCGUGCUACAGCGGUCAAGGAGCGGGGGAAGAACCGGAAGAAGGUGCUCACCCUGCUGGGCCUCUCGAGCCUGGUGGGUGUGACAUGGGGGUUGGCCAUCUUCACCCCGUUGGGCCUCUCCACCGUCUACAUCUUUGCACUUUUCAACUCCUUGCAAGGUGUCUUCAUCUGCUGCUGGUUCACCAUCCUUUACCUCCCAAGUCAGAGCACCACAGUCUCCUCCUCUACUGCAAGAUUGGACCAGGCCCACUCCGCAUCUCAAGAAUAGGAAGGCACGGCCCUGCAAUAUGGACUCAGCUCUGGCUCUCUGUGUGACCUUGGGCAGCUCCGUGCCUCUCUCUGUACUCCCUCAGUUUCCUUCUCUGUACAAUGUGGCUGGGGAGGGAGAGGAUGGGACCAGGUUGGACCACGUGGCAUCAGAGGUCCCAUCCAGAUCCAACUAUAGGUCCAAGAGUCCACGUAAGCAGGUUUGCAAGGCUCUAAAGUUCCUAUAGUCCUGAGACCCCCUGCCAGCAAAGAGUGACAGUCACCUCCAUGCCCUGCCCUCAUUGCAAAGCCCUCACUCACCUUCUGGUCUCAGCAAGGGAGGAGAGUCUGUUGCUGGCAUAGCCCUGGAAGGAGCCCCCAGCCUCUCCCCUCCUCCUCCUUGUCACUGGCCUCCCACAACUCCCCUUCUGGCUGCCUGUAACCUUGAGGGGCAUUCAGGAGGCCAGCGUUCCCUCAGGCACUGGGGGUUUGUUUUGGGGGGUGGGAGUUGAUCCUCCCACCCAGUCUGCCCCUGGUCUCUGCCCAUCCAAUCAGAGCCCACCCUCCUGGAAGAGACCCCCGUGUUCAGAGUGCUGGCAGCCCUGCACGUGUCCAGGGACACUGCAUUUCAAAGAACCACUGAGUGGGUGAGCUACCUUGGGCAAACCCCCCACUCCUGACUCUGACUGCCACGUGGGUGGCCCGACCUCUGACCUGCUGUCAUCGUAGAGGUAGAAAGCAAACAAUCUGGGGCUCAGCACACCUGGGGGUGCUCCCACUCAUUCAGUGUGUGGGGCCCCUGAGCAGAGGCUGGGCAUUGCCACUAGGACCUGAGCUCCUAGAGAACAAGGACCUGGGUGGCCUCGCUUACUGUUCCAGCCCAGGCCAAGCACAGGGUCUGGCUCGUGGCAAACCUUGAAUAAAUAUUUGUUGGCUGAA